GUAUCUGAAGAAAGAUUUGGCCAGGGGCAGCUGUGCUGGCUUAUGCUCUUCUCCUUCUGCUGCUGCCAUCCUCCAGCAAGAUGCUAGGGUCUUUGGGGCUUUGGGCAUUACUUCCCACAGCUGUGGAAGCACCCCCAAACAGGCGAACCUGUGUGUUCUUUGAGGCCCCUGGAGUGCGGGGAAGCACAAAGACACUGGGAGAGCUGCUAGAUACAGGCACAGAGCUCCCCAGAGCUAUCCGCUGCCUCUACAGCCGCUGCUGCUUUGGGAUCUGGAACCUGACCCAAGACCGGGCACAGGUGGAAAUGCAAGGAUGCCGAGACAGUGAUGAGCCAGGCUGUGAGUCCCUCCACUGUGACCCAAGUCCCCGAGCCCACCCCAGCCCUGGCUCCACUCUCUUCACCUGCUCCUGUGGCACUGACUUCUGCAAUGCCAAUUACAGCCAUCUGCCUCCUCCAGGGAGCCCUGGGACUCCUGGCUCCCAGGGUCCCCAGGCUGCCCCAGGUGAGUCCAUCUGGAUGGCACUGGUGCUGCUGGGGCUGUUCCUCCUCCUCCUGCUGCUGCUGGGCAGCAUCAUCUUGGCCCUGCUACAGCGAAAGAACUACAGAGUGCGAGGUGAGCCAGUGCCAGAGCCAAGGCCAGACUCAGGCAGGGACUGGAGUGUGGAGCUGCAGGAGCUGCCUGAGCUGUGUUUCUCCCAGCAGGUAAUCCGGGAAGGAGGUCAUGCAGUGGUUUGGGCCGGGCAGCUGCAAGGAAAACUGGUUGCCAUCAAGGCCUUCCCACCGAGGUCUGUGGCUCAGUUCCAAGCUGAGAGAGCAUUGUACGAACUUCCAGGCCUACAGCACGACCACAUUGUCCGAUUUAUCACUGCCAGCCGGGGGGGUCCUGGCCGCCUGCUCUCUGGGCCCCUGCUGGUACUGGAACUGCAUCCCAAGGACUGUGUGUGUCUCUGUCCACGUGGAAGAGCUCCCCACAACUCACUUUGCCCUAUUGGCUCCCUGUGCCACUACUUGACCCAGUACACCAGUGACUGGGGAAGUUCCCUGCGGAUGGCACUGUCCCUGGCCCAGGGCCUGGCAUUUCUCCAUGAGGAGCGCUGGCAGAAUGGCCAAUAUAAACCAGGUAUUGCCCACCGAGAUCUGAGCAGCCAGAAUGUGCUCAUUCGGGAAGAUGGAUCGUGUGCCAUUGGAGACCUGGGCCUUGCCUUGGUGCUCCCUGGCCUCACUCAGCCCCCUGCCUGGACCCCUACUCAACCACAAGGCCCAGCUGCCAUCAUGGAAGCUGGCACCCAGAGGUACAUGGCACCAGAGCUCUUGGACAAGACUCUGGACCUACAGGAUUGGGGCAUGGCCCUCCGACGAGCUGAUAUUUACUCUUUGGCUCUGCUCCUGUGGGAGAUACUGAGCCGCUGCCCAGAUUUGAGGCCUGACAGCAGUCCACCACCCUUCCAACUGGCCUAUGAGGCAGAACUGGGCAAUACCCCUACCUCUGAUGAGCUAUGGGCCUUGGCAGUGCAGGAGAGGAGGCGUCCCUACAUCCCAUCCACCUGGCGCUGCUUUGCCACAGACCCUGAUGGGCUGAGGGAGCUCCUAGAAGACUGUUGGGAUGCAGACCCAGAAGCACGGCUGACAGCUGAGUGUGUACAGCAGCGCCUGGCUGCCUUGGCCCAUCCUCAAGAGAGCCACCCCUUUCCAGAGAGCUGUCCACGUGGCUGCCCACCUCUCUGCCCAGAAGACUGUACUUCAAUUCCUGCCCCUACCAUCCUCCCCUGUAGGCCUCAGCGGAGUGCCUGCCACUUCAGCGUUCAGCAAGGCCCUUGUUCCAGGAAUCCUCAGCCUGCCUGUACCCUUUCUCCUGUGUAAAUAUGCAGUUUAUGUGUCAUCAAUGUACAUGCCAACAUAAAUAUGGCGAUUGUAUAGCUGUCUUGUCUGCCUCAUCACUGCAUUUCCCACCUGCCGAAUCCUUGGAUUCUUCUGCGGGCAUCCAGUCCACAUCAGUUCUGACCAGUGACUUGGGGUAGGUGUGCACAGGAAAGAGAAUAAAGUCAGCUUUCCUGAUGCA